UGGUCUCGAUCUCUUAACCUUGUGAUCCGCCCAGCUCGGCCUCCCAAAGUGCUGGGAUUACAGGCGUGAGCCACGGAGCCCGGCCCUCUGAUUCUUUUUGUCUAUCACUCUGUGCACUCAUUCAUUCAAGACAUUUAUGUAGGUGCCCCGCGUUCCUCUGCAGUUCUCCACUACUCUGGCUUUUCUCUAAUACAAUUUAUUUUGUGUUAUUAUUUCUUUAAGACAGAGUCUCACUCUGUCGCCCAGGCUGGAGUGCAGUGGUGCGAUCUCGGCUCACUGCAACCUCUGCCUCCCAGGUUCAAGAGAUUCUCCUGCCUCAGCCUCCCGAGUAGCCAGGACUACAGGCGUGCGCCACCACACCUGGCUAAUGUUUUUGUAUUUUUUGAUAGAGACGGGGUUUCACCAUGUUGCUCAGGCUGGUUGCGAACUCCUGACCUCGAAUGAUCCCCCACCUUGGCCUCCCAAAGUGCUGGGAUUACAGGCAUGAGCCGCCACGCCCGGCUAAUUUUUGGUAUUUGUAGUAGAAACGGGGUUUCACCAUGUUAGCCAGGCUGGGUGCGAACUCCUGACCUCAGGUAGUCCACCCGCCUUGGCCUCCCAAAGUGCUGGGAUUACAGGCGUGAGCCACCGCAGUCCGGCCCUAAUAUAGUUUUUAAAUUCAUUCAUUCCAAGGCUUUUGGGAGGCGCUCAGUGGCGUGCAGUUUCCUCUCGAAUUUCUUUCUUCCCGCAGUCUUUCUGGGCGGGCGUCUCCCGUCUGUUUCUUCCCAUCUUCCCCCUUAUCAUCCUGGGACUGGAUAAUUCUUGAAUAGUCUGGGAGGUAGCAGGGAACCCGAGUUCGGAGCCUCGACCAGAACCUCCAGACGGGAAAUUGGAGCAGGUGGUGUCGUUCCAGGACGCUGAGGACCACCUCCUCCCCUAACGCACAGCCCAACGAUCCUAAAAGUUUCUUCCCCAGGGAACAGAGCUUGAGCCGGGGGCCACCCCCCCGUCCUACCGGAGUUCUGAGGUGCGGUCAGGCGCGGAGAGCGGACGCCCAGCGCCAGAUUCUGUGGGCUCCGGAGUUCAGGCCCACUGAGCCGCAGCUGAGCACAGGCGGGGCAGGAAAAAGGAUGAGGUGAGGGAAGGCGCUGGGUUCCUGGAACCCCAAGGGAGCACUGAGCUGAGUACGUAUCGCUUGGGAUCCAGGUGUCCUUGUUUUAGGAUGUCUGACAGGUGUCCCCAGGGUAUGAGAAGUGGGACUGGGCACCCCCUAUUUGCUUUUUUUUUUUUUUUUUGAGACAGACCACAUGUUUCCUAUCUUGGAAAAUGGUACCACUUCCUUGUGCAAGCCUACCCCUGUUCCCUCACCCCUCGUUCAGUCCAACAGCAAAUCUGUCCAGUCUUCUAACUGUAUCUCAGGUUCAUUAGCCCCGCUUCCUCGUCCCUGCUCGUCUUCUGCCGGACCAGUCCGCCAUCUUGUGACCGGACUCGGGAAUAGCGUCCUACUUCCCGGCGGCCUCCACUCUUGACCCAAAUGCAAUGUGCAGCCAUGGCAAUCUUUUAUAAACAGAAAUCCGAUCAAGUUACUCCUCUGCCGAAAUCCCUCUGGUCAGUGGUUUAACUGUCGAGGUGCUCCUGGCAGCACUCUGCCCUCCCCACAUCAUUGCUGGUGGACUUGUCUCCCCUACUAGACUGUGCCCUGUGAGGGUGGAGACUUUGUGCAGGGUUGUAUCCCCAACAUCUGAUGCAGUGAUUCAAUAAACAUCUGUCCAAUUAAUAGGAAAGACAGUUCCUUUUCUCAUUCCCCUAUUGCUGGUCCCCUGCCCUCAAGCAGGAUGUUAUGCCCCAGAGUGGCUGUGGGUGCGAACAUUCUGCCCCUCUGGCUGGUCUGGCACUGAUUUCCACCCUGAGCUGGUGUUGCCUCUCUCCUUCCUCUUGGCCAACCUCUCUUCCACCAAUAUAAGCCCAAACUGGAGGCCAGCAGGCAGUCAUGCGUUUUAUGGCAGGCCCUGCAGGGAGCCAGAGUCUGGGUCCCCUGUGCUUCCACAGCAGCCCCCAAGCCCUCUACACGGUCCUCUUAAUAGUGCUGGUCAUGAUGAGCUUGGUGUUUGGUAAGUUUGUUCCUGUCAAUUGGGAACCCCCUCAACCACUUCCAUUCCCCAAAUACCUGCGCUGCUACCGAUGCCUCUUGGAGACCAAGGAGUUAGGGUGCCUUCUGGGAUCUGACAUCUGCCUCACCCCAGCUGGCAGCAGCUGCAUCACUCUCCACAAAAAGAACAGCAGCGGUUCUGACGUCAUGGUGAGUGACUGCCGAAGUAAGGAGCAGAUGAGUGAUUGUUCAAAUACCCGAACUUCUCCGGUGUCUGGCUUCUGGAUAUUCUCUCAAUACUGCUUCCUGGAUUUCUGCAAUGACCCUCAAAACAGAGGGCUCUAUACUCCUUAGUGUGACUGCAGCAAACUUUGGUGUAAAAUUCCACCAGUUUCCAGCCACCUUCCUGACUUCUAUCUGGGCUUGGCCAGGACUUCUAGUCCCUCACACCAGCCCUCCUUGCCUCCCUCCAGCCACUGGACCCCAGCCUUGGCUCUUCCUCUUGGUUGACGCCCUUCAGCACACUUACUGCUACUCUGUACCCCCAGCCCUACUGCCCACCAGGUUUCCUCUCUUGUCCCCUAGUCCCUGGAUGUUUCUCCCAAAUAAAUUUGUGUGUAAACUGUU